GAGUCCCAGGCGUGCGGCUGGCCAUGGCGCUGUUCUACGUCGCGCGGUACCCGGGCCCCGAUGCGGCAGCUGCGGCGGGGCCGGAGGGCGCGGAGGCCGGGGCGCACGGCAGGGCCCGCGCGCUGCUCGAGCGGCUGCAGAGCCGGGCCCGCGAACGGCAGCAGCAGCGGGAGCCCGCGCAGACCGAGGCGGCUGCAUCGACCGAGCCGGCGACCAGGAGGCGACGGCGGCCCCGGCGGCGGCGGCGGGUGAACGACGCGGAGCCGGGGAGCCCGGAGGCGCCGCAGGGAAAGCGACGGAAGGCGGACGGCGAGGACGCGGGCGCAGAAAGCAACGAGGAGGCGCCAGGGGAGCCCAGCGCAGGGAGCAGCGAGGAGGCGCCAGGGGAGCCCAGCGCAGGGAGCAGCGAGGAGGCGCCGGGGGAGCGCAGCACCAGCGCCAGCGCCGAGGCGGCCCCAGAUGGACCGGCCCUGGAGGAGGCGGCCGGACCCCUGGUCCCCGGCCUGGUGCUGGGGGGGUUCGGGAAGAGGAAGGCGCCGAAGGUCCAGCCUUUCCUGCCAAGGUGGCUGGCUGAGCCUAACUGUGUCAGAAGGAAUGUCACCGAAGACCUGGUUCCUAUCGAGGACAUCCCUGACGUCCAUCCUGACCUGCAGAAGCAGCUGCGGGCACACGGCAUCUCGUCCUACUUUCCAGUCCAGGCAGCUGUGAUUCCUGCCCUCCUGGAGAGCGCAGCCUGUGGGUUUCUGGUGGGCAGAGGUGGCUACCGGCCUAGCGACCUCUGUGUUUCUGCCCCAACAGGCAGUGGGAAGACACUGGCCUUCGUCAUCCCUGUGGUGCAGGCCCUGCUUUCGAGAGUGGUCUGCCACAUCCGUGCCCUGGUUGUGCUGCCCACCAAGGAGCUGGCCCAGCAGGUGAGCAAAGUUUUCAACAUCUACACAGAUGCCACACCUCUGAGAGUCUCCCUGGUUACGGGACAGAAGUCUCUGGCCAAGGAGCAGGAGAGCCUCGUCCAGAAAACAGCUGAUGGGUACCGCUGCUUGGCUGACAUCGUGGUAGCCACCCCCGGCCGCCUGGUGGACCACAUCGACCAGACCCCAGGAUUCAGCCUCCAGCAGCUCCGCUUCCUGAUUAUCGACGAGGCUGACCGGAUGAUUGACAGCAUGCAUCAGUCCUGGCUGCCGCGGGUGGUGGCGGCCGCCUUCCAGAGCGAGGACCCCGCGGACCCCUGUGCCCUGCUCCAGCGAAGGCAGGCCCAGGCUGUGACAGCCGCCAGCACCUGCUGUCCCCAGAUGCCCCUGCAGAAGCUGCUCUUCUCAGCUACUCUGACCCAGAACCCUGAAAAGCUGCAGCAGCUGGGCCUCCACCAGCCCCGGCUUUUCUCCACAGGGCUAGCACACAGGGGCCUGGAAGAUACAGAUGGGGACGGGGAUUCGGGGAAGUAUGCCUUUCCUGUUGGGCUCACGCACCACUACGUGCCCUGCAGCCUCAGCUCUAAGCCGCUGGUCGUCCUGCACCUGGUCCUGGAGAUGGGCUUCUCGAGGGUUCUCUGCUUCACUAACUCCCGAGAGAACUCCCACAGGCUCUUCCUGCUGGUGCAAGCUUUUGGGGGUGUGGACGUGGCUGAGUUCUCCUCGCGCUACGGGCCUGGCCAGAGGAGGAUGAUCCUGAAGCAGUUUGAACAGGGGAAGAUCCAGCUGCUCAUCAGCACGGACGCCACCGCGCGAGGCAUCGACGUGCAGGGUGUGGAGCUGGUGGUGAACUACGACGCCCCCCAGUACCUGAGAACCUACGUGCACCGGGUUGGGAGGACAGCUCGCGCUGGGAAAACUGGACAGGCCUUCACACUGCUCCUGAAAGUGCAGGAGAGGAGAUUCCUCCGAAUGCUAACUGAAGCUGGGGCACCUGAGUUGCAGCGGCACGAGCUCUCCAGCAAGCUGCUGCAGCCGCUGGUUCCUCGGUACGAGGAGGCCCUGUCCCAGCUGGAGGAGUCUGUCAAGGAAGAGCGCAAGCAGAGGGCGGCCUAGGCUGGGGCUCAGAGGGCCGGAGGGACUGAACGCUCACCACCCUGACCCUCCUUCCAGAGCAGUGCUGAUCACUGGAUCCUGUAUGUGAGGAAAGGAAUCCCCCAGUGGACACAGCCUUCCUCCCCAAGCACGUGGUCUCUGCGCCAGGCAGCCCGGGCGUCAGAGCUCAAGCACCUGCCCCGACUGGAGACUUCAGGGCUUGUCACUUUCAGAGUGUGGAGGUCAGGAUGGCUGCGGGCAAUGAAGCCUUAGUAAAACGGUGAAAAGUACUCCCAGACGGACGCGGGCACCCGUCAUGCUUUUGCUGAGAGUUGGGGGCAUUAACCUUGAGCUAAUGUUAAAAAUCAAGCUCUUGGCCAGGCAUGGUGGCUCAUGCCUGUAAUUCCAGCACUUUGGGAGGCCAAGGCGGGUGGAUCACCUGAGGUCACGAGUUCGAGACCAGCCUGACCAACAUGGAGAAACCCUGUCUCUACUAAAAAUACAAAAUUAGCCAGGCGUGGUGGUGCAUGCCUGUAAUCCAGCUACUUGGGAGGCUGAGGCAGGAAAAUGGCUUGAACCCGGGAGGUGGAGGUUGCAGUGAGCUGAGAUUGCGCCACUGCACUCCAGCCUGGGCAACAAGAGCAAAACUCCGUCUCAAAAAAAAAAAUUGCCGGGCGCGGUGGCAAAUGCCUGUAAUCCCAGCACUUUGGGAGGCCGAGGCAGGUGGAUCACAAGGUCAGGAGAUAGAGACCAUCAUUGCUAACAUGGUGAAACCCCGUCUCUACUAAAAAUACAAAAAAAAAAAAAAAACAACUAGCCGGGCGUGGUGGCGGGCACCUAUAGUCCCAGCUACUCGGGAGGCUGAGGCAGGAGAAUGGCGUGAACCCGGGAGGCGGAGCUUGCAGUGAGCGGAGACUGCGCCACUGCACUCCAGCCUGGGCAACAGAGUGAGACUCCGUCAAAAAAAAAGCUCUCCUCCCCAGAUUUGUGAACCUUGUGACUGUUCAGUGGACACCUCACAUAUUGCUGGUGGGAAGGUCACGUGGAGACAGCUGGGCAAAGCCUUGGGGCGUUAAACACAGAGUCACUCAUGACCCAGCACUUCCUCUCCUAUGCACCUUGUACACCCCAGAUCAAUGAAACCUACAUCCACACAGAAACGUACACAAAUCUCUCAGCAGCACUGUUCACAGUAGCCAAAAACUAGAAACCACAUGUCCGUCAGCUGAUGAAUGGAGAAUAAAACGUGGGAAAUCCACACCAGGAGAGAAAAAGGAGUGAGGCACCAGCAUAGGCACCCCGUGGAUGAACCCGGAACCUGACGCUAACUGAAGGAAGGCUCCGGCUAUAGGGAGUGUCCCAGGCACAGCCAGAGAUUGAAGGGUGCCGGGGCCGGGAGUUGGUGGGGGUUGGGGCUGGGGACACAGUGGCCAGUGUGUGGGUUUGUUUUGGGGAUGAUGAAAAUGUUCUUAGGUUGUGUGUGGUGAUGGCUGCUCACCUCUAUAAACCUUUUACUAAAAACCAUGGACUGGGUGGAUACAGUGUGUGAAUUCUCUCAGUCCAGUGCUUUGUUUGAAAAAGGUGGAUGAUGCCAACAUCACUAACCGCCAGGGAGACGCAGGCCACGGCCACACCCGGCUCACUGGAGUUGUGAGGAUGGAAACACCAGCCCACCCCACUCAGUUCAGACCUCAGCUUAGAUGCAAAGAAUGUCUGGGAUGGGGACUGGCAGCUGAUUAGAGAUGCAACCACUGAACCUGUGGACUGUGUUCAAACAAAUGCCAGCAGAACACAAAAGGCGACUGUUACAGGAGGCAGAAAGAAAUGAUUUAGGUAGACGGGGUAAAGCCAGUCCCCAGCAGAAAAUUUGCCUUUUAACAAAAAGCAGCUCAAAAAUAGCUCCCUUUCUAACCUCGGGGUUCAAAAUCACUUCUCACGACAAGCAGCCAGAAAGAGCAGACUGUGAAUCACAGAUGAGACAGCUCGGGCACAGGAGUGCGGGGGGUGUCUCCUGGGUGAUCACCAAACUUCACACUUCCACAAUGGGCCCCAGUAAAACAGUGGACCCUAAUAAGCACAUUCCCGUCCCCUUAGGUGCACUAAGGGAAGCUAAAAGCAGACUGAGGGGUGCCUGUAACCCCAAGAAGAUGUCUGGGAGCAGACCCAGAGACCCUCGCAGAAAAGUGUCACAGAGCAGCACAGACUGAGUCUGACAGAAACUCUCUAUACAAAUAGCACACCUUGUCCCAGCUAAAACCCUGGGCCCUGGGAGGACAAGACAUCCCUCCUCUAACCCCUCGUCACUAGCCCAUUUGUAAAAACCUUGACAGGCCGGGCACGGUGGCUCACACCUGUAAUCCCAGCACUUUGGGAGGCUGAGGCAGGCGCAUCACCUGAGGUCAGGAGAUCGAGACCAUCCUGGCCAACAUGGUGAAACCCCAUCUCUACUAAAAAUACAAAACUUAGCUGAGCGUGGUGGCGUGUGCCUGGAGUCCCAACUACUCAAGAGGCUGAGGCAGGAGAAUCACUUGCCCGGGAGGUGGAGGUUGCAGUGGGCCAAGAUCAGCCCACUGCACUGCAGCCUGGCGACAGAAAAAAAAGAAACCUUGACAUCUUUACUACAACUUAGCAACCCGCUCAGGCCCCCUCUGCAACGGAGAGCUCUUCUUCCUUUUUGCUUAUUAAACUUCUGCUCCAAA